AGCGGAAGUCCCGCCCAGCCUAGGCCGAACUUCCGGCUCUCACUGCUAGGGGCUUAAGCGGAGGGAGUCGAGCCAGCGUCGCCGCGAUGGUGUUGUUGGAGAGCGAGCAGUUCCUGACGGAGCUGACCAGACUUUUCCAGAAGUGCCGGACGUCGGGCAGCGUCUAUAUCACCUUGAAGAAGUAUGACGGUCGAACCAAACCCAUUCCAAAGAAGGGUACUGUGGAGGGCUUUGAGCCCGCAGACAACAAGUGUCUGUUAAGAGCUACCGAUGGGAAGAAGAAGAUCAGCACUGUGGGAGAAAACCCAAUGCCACCUUUCUAAGGGAUUUCAAGAGGUGAGCUCCAAGGAAGUGAAUAAGUUUCAGAUGGCUUAUUCAAACCUCCUUAGAGCUAACAUGGAUGGGCUGAAGAAGAGAGACAAAAAGAACAAAACUAAGAAGACCAAAGCAGCAGCAGCAGCAGCAGCAGCAGCACCUGCCGCAGCAGCAACAGCACCAACAACAGCAGCAACAACAGCAGCAACAGCAGCACAGUAAAGGGCAUACAUUUCCUGCUUUCACCAAUUAACCACUGAAUUGCUAUUUUUUCCUUUUGGCCAGAUAGCUAGGUUUCUGGUUCCCCCACAGUAGGUGUUUUCACAUAAGAUUAGGGUCCUUUUGGAAAGAAUAGUUGCAGUGUUUAUAGGAUAGUUGUGGUAAGAAUCUAGUUUAUUUUGCAUUUGGCUAAUUGGUCUGUGCUGCAUGGUUAUAUACUCCUGGAUUAUAGAUUAAAAGUCUCUGUAGACAUCUCUGUGAAGAGCAAGCUAUCAUUAAACAUGUCUGUUUAUCAGCACUGUCUCUUUAUUCCUUUCCCAACCCAUUUUAAUAGUUCUGGCAAUAACUACUAAAUCUAGAAUGAUGUGAUUAAUGAAUAGGCUUUAGCUCUAUAAUAUCUUCUAGGUUAUUAGAAUUGAAACCUGACAGUUUUAUAAAAAGUCAUGUUAUCUCAUGAGCUGCUUCCCACCUGGCUGUAUAAUUUUAUCAUCAUGGUUCCCCAGUUUCGAUGAGUUCUCACAGUCAAAUGAGAGUUUGUUUAACCACCUUAGGAGAAACAUACUACAAAGUCAUCAAGAAUAAAGGUUCCAAAGUAAUUAUGAUUUUUGGUUUCUUUAUGCCCUUUGGUUUGGAUAUUUUCAUGUGC